ACUCCCUCCCGCGGGCCCAGCCGAACCGCGGCCGCGCUUCCUGCACCCGGGACCCGACAGAGGUGAGUGCGCCGGGCGGCCGGGGCGAGGGUUGACGGCGGCGCCAGCGCGGGGACGCACCCGGGAACGGCUGACCUUCAGCGAGGCCGGCUCCCCGCCAGCUACCGGGGCGGAAAAUUCAAAUCCAAUCUGUGGAAUAAAGGCCUUCGGGGGAAGUGGAGCAGGAGAAGGACUGGGAGACAGAUUCUUGCUAUGGCUAUGGCUACAGUCUUACCCAAGCUCUUCUUGAAGCCCCGGCCUCAAGUGAUCCUCCCACCUCAACCUCCCAAGGUGCUGAGAUUACAGGCAUGAGCCAUCAUGUCCAGCCUUCAACCAGAUUUCUUGACAGCACCUUUAUAUGUGAUUCUUACACCAAUCUUCAUUGUUAACCCCAUUUUAAAGAAGCAGAAACCAAGGCCCAGGGAGGCUACAUAACUUGCCAGAGCUCUCAGAGCCAAAAAGCAACAGAUGUGGAAUUCAAACCCGGGCAUUCAGAUGCCCAAGUUCCCUGCACUCCCACUCUCCCAAACUGCCUCAGCCUGAGCAAGCCCAACCUGAAGCCUUCCUCCUGGAGUCCAAAGUCCAGCCAGGAAUGUGACAUGGGCUCCCCAGCCCUCCAGAUGUGUGUGCUCACACUUUGUCUGGACUUGUUCCUCCUUGGCCUUCGAACGUUCUGCCCUCAGAUGUCCCCAUUAGUCACAGUCUGUCUGAGAGCCCUCGGAUUAGCUGGAUGGGAGCAGACGCAACUUUGUGGUGGUCAUCAGGUUGUCCCAUUCAUCAGCUCAGGCCUGAGCCUGCUGGAGUGUGGUCGUUGCCAGAAACAAUAACUCUUAGGAAAGAAAACCAGCCUCUUUCUGCCUGAAACUGUCCUGAGAGGUGCUUGACUCAGCAUCGGCAAUUAUUUCCCAGAAGGAAAGUUACCGACCUGAUUCGGCAGCCGCGUGCUCCGCUCUAGAAAGCUCAUGGUGACGGGAAGCACAGGACAGGGGUGGAUCAGCAAGAGAAGGCUUGGGCCUGAGCAGAGACUGAGAUGAGCUGGCGCUAGAACCGAGGGAGGAAGUAGGGACUCAUUCUGUUGUUUAGGGGAUAAAGAGAGAUUUCCGCGAAGGCUAGCCAGCUGUGCUAAUUGGAAGAACGAAGUGGAAAAACAGUGAUUUUCAAAAGUAGAUCAUCUGUGCACAUUCUGAAAUAUAUGCACAUUUUUCCAUUAGUAUGAGUUUGCAGUGAGGAUGUAUCUGAUGCAUCCGUUUCUGUAUCAGUCAGACUCAGCAGGAAGCAGAUGGCACCCUCAAGCAGGGUAACUGAUGAGAGUUUAACACAAAGGUGUGGACAGGGUUAAGGGAUGGUGCCACACGGUGGGACGGCCAUGCCUCAGGAGCUGUUACUAGCCCUAGGCUUGCAGGAAGAAGGAAGAGACAAGUGCAGGACAGGGACUCCAACAGGAACUGAGCUGACAUCUUCAGCCGAGGGAGGCAGCCAACCUGAAGUGACCCUGGCAGAGUGGAUAAAUACUGCCGGGUCUUCACUCUCCUCCCAUCCUCUGAUCUCCAGUUAGUGCUUCCUAUCACCCAAAUCUAACAGACGCUGGAAGGCAGGGUGCCGGGUGACAUCAUCCUUAGAGUAGGGGGAUGGAGACUGGAUCUGGAUAGGUGGAUAGAAAGUAUGCAGCACAUUGCUGGUGCAGGAGCCUCUUUCACACAUUCCUUUGGCUGCCAUUUUCUGGACACCUGCAGUGUGUCACUCUGGGUUUGACACUGGGGAAAUGCAGUGAAUGAGCUGUCCUCAGGCUCUGUGUAGAGAUUCUGCCUUUACAGAUGCCAGGAUAAAAAGAAAAUCCCACAAGUGACUGGAAAAGAAGAAAUGGAUGCAAACAUCACUGGCACUGGGGGUGGUGAAUUUCAGACCAUGUCUCUGGAGCCCAGCCCAAUGUGGGAGAUAAUUUCUGUGGGCGAGACAGAUAGUUAUUAGUGCAGCAUUUCCAAUCAGCAUUUCAAAAGCGUAGGUCAUAAUUUACAUUCUCUAGGCUCAGGAAGGUUCUGGAAGACAAUAUGUGCUUAAUUUACCAUUAGUGAGCUGUUUUGUUGCUUGUAAAGCCAGGUUUUAUUUACAAAACAACAAAUUCUGCUGUCUCUGCCAAGGACUGGACAUCUUGACACCAAGAAACAUAGCAAAAUCCAGUCAAAAGUGACUUUGCAAGCAGUAUGAUGAAUUUCUAUAUGGUUCUCCAGCUCCAGCAUUUUCUUAGGGAAAGCAUGGCCAGAAAUGCCCAAGUCUGUAUUUUGGCAACAGCCCAAGCUUCUCAGACUCCACUGGCCAGUUCCAGAUCUUUAAGUAACUAUAAUAAGAGCCAUGCUGUCUGUCUCUAAAAAGUGAAGCAUGAAUCAAAAGUGACUUUGUUUUAAUUUAACAGCAUUGAGACUGUGAAAGGCACUGGAUAUGUUUAGGCACCUGUAAACGGAGAAUGUGGGGUGAAAAAAGAGAGGCAUAGCUGGGUGCGAUGGCUCACGCCUGUAAUCCCAGCACUUUGGGAGGCUGAAGCAGGCAGAUCACUUGAGGCCAGGAGUUUGAGACCAGCCUGGCCAACACGGUAAAACCCCGUCUCUACUAAAAAUACUAAAAAUUAGCUGGGUGUGGUGGCACACGUCUGUAAUCCCAGCUACUUAGGAGGCUGAGGCAUGAACAUUGCUUGAACCCAGGAGGCCGAGAUUGCAGUGAGCCAAGAUCAUGCCACUGCACUCCAGCCUGGGUGACAGAGGGAGACUCUGUCUCAACAAAAGAAAAGAAAAAGAGAGGCAGGAGACAGGGCCACCAAGUACUGGCACACUGUGCCAACUCCAGGGACCACCAACUGAUAGAUUGCAGCAUGCACGGCACCCUUGAGGUUGUGCAGUGUGGUAGCCCUGGCAGGAUUCAUUCUGUAAUACAUUUUCUACAGGGCAUGCUCUGUACUCCUGAUAGUCAGAGUCCUCGAUCUGGCAACUGACAAUGAGCUUUAAAACAGCCCACCUCUUUCCUAGAGAGAUAAGACGAGGCAGAACAGAAUCAUUGGAAGAAACAGCUUCAGAGUCAGAACUCCUGUCAAGUCCUGGCUCAGUCACUUGGGAAUUGAGUGGCCUCAGGCAAUUUAUGAAACCUCAGUUUCCUGAUCUGUGAAAUGGAGAGAAUAAAACUACUUGUUUUGGAGAUGAAAAGAGAUCAUGCACAGGCACUAAGGACACAGGAAGCAUUUACAAGAUAAGAGCAAUUGAGCCUGCAGUGAGCCGCCACUGUACUCCACUGUACUCUGGGGGACGACAAAGUGAGACCCUGUUUCAAAAAUAAAUAAAUAAAUAAUAAAUGAUAAGAGCUGCAAAUAAGAGGAUAUUUGGAAUGUCCAAUGACAGUGAUAAUAACAGCUAACAUCUAUUGAACCCUCAUGUGUGCUGGGCCUUGAGCUAAGGGCUUUACUUGGUUUAACUCAUGUAAUCAUCUUAGCCCUCAUUUGAAGAUGUGUCUCCAUUUCACAGAUGGAAACAGGCACAGAGAGGUUAAAAGACUUGUCCAGGGUCACCCUACUAGCGCGUAGUACAACUGGAAUUCAAAUGCUGACACUGGCUUUCAACGCCAAACUCUUCACAACUACAUUCAGUUUGGCAACUUUUAGAAAGCAGAUGUGAAUUUUUAUGGCAUAGUCAACCCAGAAAAUUCCACUUGUGAGGACUUUCUAAGGAGGAAUUUCAAAAUGAAGACCAGCAGAGGAGGCUUAUCCAGCCUCUUAGCCUGCUGGGAUGUUGCUGGGGUAGUGCCCAGUGAGAAAAGCAAAUCCUCCCGCCUCCACACUCCCUGUGCCUCUCUCUGCCUCCUCCUGCUCCCCGGCCUUCCCCCGCUAGGGCACCUUCUGUCCUCUUACCCACUGUCCAUCCUUCUGGAGAUUCACCUAGAGGCUAAGUCACACCGUGUGGAGCACUGAGCCACCUAGAGGGGUUAGCAGAAGGUGAGAUGUUUGCUCUCUUUCUCCUUCUACCUCCCCUGCCUGCAGUUCCAAUCACCCUUCAUCCCUAACCUGCAACCAUCUGUCCUGACAACCGCCCAACCUUCUGCAGACUCUUGCCGUGACAGUUCCAGACAUUCAUUUCACAAAUAGGAAUGGGGGCACCCUGCUUUGAGCAGGAUAACUGGGCUGAGAGCAAGGGCCCUGUAGAGAGACAGCUGUGUGCCAGCGACCCCAGCGGCAGUGCAAUGCUGGGAAAGGGGCUAAGGGCACACAGCAGGGUUCAGCACACAUUACCUGGGGCAACCAAGAAUGCUCCCUAGGGGAAGUGACUUGGGGUCUUAAGAUGGGGGCAGGAGUUCAGGAGGUGGGAAACAGGAGGUCUAUAGAGUGGGGAGGGCCACAGGAGCCAAGGUAUGCAAUUGUGAAAGAGCAGAAGGAAACAGCCAAGGGUGGCUUGGGACAGGAUGUGGGUAGGAGGAGGGCUUCUGUACCCAACUGCCUGGAUUUGAAUCCCGAGGCCUCUACGUACCACCUGUGUGACCUUGGGCAAGUUGUUUGCCCUCUCUGUGCCUCAUUCCCCUAUGUAUAAGAUGGGAAUAACAAUACUGUCUACAUCAUAGAGCCCUGAACAUCAAAUGAGUUAAUGUAAUUAAGUACUUAACAACAGAGCCCAGCACACAGCUGUGCUCAAUAGAUGCGGGCUGGGACUAUUAUUACUAUUAUCUGUGAGGAUGUGGGGCAGAGGGGCCUAAGGCCUCCUUGAAUUAUCAAGAAGGUCAGUAGGAGGUCCUCUAAGCCAUCCCUGCGGCAGACAGGCUCCGGCUCUGAGGAGCACCGGGCAGGGACCCAGGAGGCUGCAAACCUAAGUGCAGAUCCCCAGGCUGGGCUGGACAGGCUGAGGUCAGGGCAGGUGCAGAGAGGCCCAGAGCUGCAACACCGCACUUCAUUUAUUGCGUGGCUACUGAUUUGCCCGUGCUGGGCACACGGACGUGGUAAAGGACAGAAGGGCUACUCCUGGACUGUUCUCUGGGCUUCUCACCCUGCGGUUGUGGUGAGAGGCUGCUGACAGCCAGGGCACCCGGGAGUGGGCGUGGCUGGAGAAGGACCCCUGUCCUUUUACAGCUAGGCCCACUCUGAGCCCCACGCAGUGUUCUAGAGCCUGUCCCCCCAGGGCAGGAUGGUAGUGGGGGCAGGGGUCCCUGAGCCAUUGCGGCCCUUCCCGGCAGGCGCCAAGCCUAGGGGCUGUGGUCAGCGUGAAAGGCAGGGCAUGGACCCUCACUCAGGGCUGCGUGUGCCCGACGUGGGUGGGGGGGGCGUGGAAUCGGAGCACAACUUGGCCCUGCGUUCCCAGGAAGGGACCCGAAGACCUCCCCAGGCCACCCCGCCAUCUGCGUGCGCGCUGGCAAGAGGAGGGGCGCGGGGUAAUGGUGGCCGGCGCCACAGCCCCGCGCCGCGCAGGGUCUUGCCCACCACCAGCGAUGCCCAGCCCUUGGUAGAGCUUGAACCACCUUCUAUAAACAGGAUGGCGGUGGAGAGACAGGCCCAGUCCCUGAGCCCAUGAGGAGUGUGGCCCCUUCAGGCCCAAAGAUGGGGAACAUCACUGCAGACAACUCCUCGAUGAGCUGUACCAUCGACCAUACCAUCCACCAGACGCUGGCCCCGGUGGUCUAUGUUACCGUGCUGGUGGUGGGCUUCCCGGCCAACUGCCUGUCCCUCUACUUCGGCUACCUGCAGAUCAAGGCCCGGAACGAGCUGGGCGUGUACCUGUGCAACCUGACGGUGGCCGACCUCUUCUACAUCUGCUCGCUGCCCUUCUGGCUGCAGUACGUGCUGCAGCACGACAACUGGUCUCACGGCGACCUGUCCUGCCAGGUGUGCGGCAUCCUCCUGUACGAGAACAUCUACAUCAGCGUGGGCUUCCUCUGCUGCAUCUCCGUGGACCGCUACCUGGCUGUGGCCCAUCCCUUCCGCUUCCACCAGUUCCGGACCCUGAAGGCGGCCGUCGGCGUCAGCGUGGUCAUCUGGGCCAAGGAGCUGCUGACCAGCAUCUACUUCCUGAUGCACGAGGAGGUCAUCGAGGACGAGAACCAGCACCGCGUGUGCUUUGAGCACUACCCCAUCCAGGCAUGGCAGCGCGCCAUCAACUACUACCGCUUCCUGGUGGGCUUCCUCUUCCCCAUCUGCCUGCUGCUGGCGUCCUACCAGGGCAUCCUGCGCGCCGUGCGCCGGAGCCACGGCACCCAGAAGAGCCGCAAGGACCAGAUCCAGCGGCUGGUGCUCAGCACCGUGGUCAUCUUCCUGGCCUGCUUCCUGCCCUACCACGUGUUGCUGCUGGUGCGCAGCGUCUGGGAGGCCAGCUGCGACUUCGCCAAGGGCGUUUUCAACGCCUACCACUUCUCCCUCCUGCUCACCAGCUUCAACUGCGUCGCCGACCCCGUGCUCUACUGCUUCGUCAGCGAGACCACCCACCGGGACCUGGCCCGCCUCCGCGGGGCCUGCCUGGCCUUCCUCACCUGCUCCAGGACCGGCCGGGCCAGGGAGGCCUACCCGCUGGGUGCCCCCGAGGCCUCCGGGAAAAGCGGGGCCCAGGGUGAGGAGCCCGAGCUGUUGACCAAGCUCCACCCGGCCUUCCAGACCCCUAACUCGCCAGGGUCGGGCGGGUUCCCCACGGGCAGGUUGGCCUAGCCUGGGUCCUCCGCGGGUGGCUCCACGUGAGGCCUGAGCCUUCAGCCCACGGGCCUCAGGGCCUGCCGCCUCCUGCUUCCCUCGCUGCGGAGGCAGGGAAGCCCCUGUAACUCCGGAAGCCUGCUCUCGCUUGCUGAGCCCGCUGGGACCGCCGAGGGUGGGAAUAAGCCCCGGUUGGCUCGUGGGAAUAAGCCGUGUCCUCUGCCGCGGCUGCGAUGUGGCCAGGCUGGGGCUGCUGGUCGGGGGAAGACAGUGAACUGCGUUCCCUGGCCUGCUUCCUGCAGAGUUUGUGCAUGGGGAGUGUGAGGACAUGGAGGGUGGGAGGCUGGGCGUUCAGCUGCCAGGGCCUUCCAAUGCCACCGUUGUCACAGACAAUGCCUGUCCAAACGUCCCGGUGGGAUCAGCACUGCAGCCCGCCCACAACAGGGUGGGAAGGGAAGACUGGAGGGGGAAGGAAGGCAGGAGGGGGAAGGAAGAAAGAGGGGGAAGGAAAGAAAGAGGGGGGAAGGAAAGGAGGAAGGGGAGAAGGAAGGGAGGAGGAAAGAAGGAAGGUAGGGGGUGUUGGGUUGGGAGAAUUGAGGGAGUUAUAGGCAGAGGAGGAUCCUAGCUCCAGCCAUAAGAACUGGGAGAGCCGCCUGCUGCUCCAGAAGACCUGCCCACCUCCACAGAAAUGCUAGCCCUUCAGACCUUCUGGUCAGUGAACUGGGACCAGCUCUGACUAAGGAUGCCUUCCAUGGCCUGGGACUCGAGUUCUUCAGAACCAAGAGGCUAACUGGGCUUCCUCCAAGAAGGGACCAGGGGCUAGAAGCAGAAGUUGGCAUCAGCAAACAUUUCUGGAAUCUACCAAAGGGAGGCCCAGGCAGAACCCCUUCCUCAGUCUCCCUUCCCCUCUUCCCCCCAGCCUUGAAGAGGUUGAUCCUUUGUGCUGUGUCUCUUAGCCCUUUCAUCGGGGAUGCCCAGAGGCAACAGCCCAGGCUGGAGGUGCCCCAGGGAAGGGUGCUCACAGUGGUCCCAGGGCUACACUUGGCUUUGACUGCACAGCCCCUGCUCAGAUCCUUGUGGAGGGUGUCCGAUGACUUGGGGAGGUUCUCUUCCCCUUCCUAGAGGAGGAAGUGACCAAGUUUGAAGGCGGCAGAAAUGGCCACACAGCCAAGAAGAGCCCAUGCAACUCAGUCCAGGAUUUUACUGGGUCAGUGACAUUGGUGGAAGCCUUCAUGCCUCCUCAUUCCACAGCACUUCCUCCUAUGUUGACCUUAAACACUGGCUUCCCACUGAUACAGACUGGGAUGAGCUGAGGGCAGUCUCAUUUACUGUCAAGAGUUGUAUUUUUGUAUUGUCCUUUUUGCCAAGUCUACAUGUGUUGACUCUGUAAUGGAUUUAUGUAGCCCACUUCAGUCUGCAAAUAAAGCAAAGUAACUGGA